GCCCAUCCUUUUAGCACCGCGAGAGGCGCCGGUGUUUCGAGCCGUGGCACCGGCAUCGGCUGACACUGCUGCCUCCAGCUAGUUAUUUCGUCCUCUUCCGUUCUUCACCCCUACACCUUGGAGGUGAACUUCUCACCUGAGGGCUGUAAAGACUCGUUUGAAAAUGGAGAGCCAAGAACCAACGGAAUCUUCUCAGAAUGGCAAACAGUAUAUCAUUUCAGAGGAGUUAAUUUCAGAAGGAAAAUGGGUCAAGCUUGAAAAAACAACGUACAUGGAUCCUACUGGUAAAACUAGUGUUUGGGAUGGGACCUUCAGUGCUUUUCCCAGCACUGUCUUCUUCAGUCUUUAGGACUAACCUUAGGAGGCAGCAGAGAGAGCUAUGCCAAAAGAACUUGGGAAUCAGUGAAACGUACAACCAGGAAAGAGCAGACUGCGGAUGGUGUCGCGGUCAUCCCCGUGCUGCAGAGAACACUUCACUAUGAGUGUAUCGUUCUGGUGAAACAGUUCCGACCACCAAUGGGGGGCUACUGCAUAGAGUUCCCUGCAGGUCUCAUAGAUGAUGGUGAAACCCCAGAAGCAGCUGCUCUCCGGGAGCUUGAAGAAGAAACUGGCUACAAAGGGGACAUUGCCGAAUGUUCUCCAGCGGUCUGUAUGGACCCAGGCUUGUCAAACUGUACUAUACACAUCGUGACAGUCACCAUUAACGGAGAUGAUGCCGAAAACGCAAGGCCGAAGCCAAAGCCAGGGGAUGGAGAGUUUGUGGAAGUCAUUUCUUUACCCAAGAAUGACCUGCUGCAGAGACUUGAUGCUCUGGUAGCUGAAGAACAUCUCACAGUGGACGCCAGGGUCUAUUCCUACGCUCUAGCACUGAAACAUGCAAAUGCAAAGCCAUUUGAAGUGCCCUUCUUGAAAUUUUAAGCCCAAAUAUGACACUGGCCAUUUUUGUAAACGAGACCACCAGGCCUUCUUCACUAAGACUUUGUAUUCAACUUAGUUUAAUGUAGAUUUGCCAUUAGCUUUUUCGUAAAAUAAAAGCACAGAACAGAUGUGGUGGUGGUAUGGAAUUGUAAUUACAGGUAGGUUGUGACCUUCCUUUAAAUUUGUUAUAACUCCAGCUAAAAUUAACAAAGAAUAUAAAUGCAAGUAUGUUUACUCCAAUUUUUUUAAAGCUCAACAGCAGUUAACUACAGCUCAGUUACUUUUCUAGUCCAGUCUGGUAGACAGGGGUAUUUGUAUAGAGAAAUAGACCUGAGUUCUCAAUUAGGUCAUUUCCACUCUCAACCCCCAAUAUAAAAUUCUAAGCUGGGUAUGCAAAUAACCAUGUACUCCGUUAGUGUUUAAAACAGCGUUAAAAAGAAAAAAAAGGCUUUUUGGCCUCUUCUAAUUGAAUUUUUACUAUGCAAAAUUUAUCUAGGGUAGUUGAAUCCAACUAGGGUAGGGUUCGAUAGAAUCCUCUACUAGUUUUCAGUUCAUCUAUUUACUGAGGCUGAACCAGCUUUUAAGUAAGGAAAACGGUUGACUCCAUUCACUACACCAAGGCUAGGAGACUAAUGAAAAUUCAGGUCCAUCCCGCAAGCAUCUGCACGUGCUUGAGGAUCUCUUUUCCUAUUCUUACCUCAAAGAGUACUUGAAGUUUCUGAAAACAAAUCUGUAAGACUGACAUGUUUGGGGCAGUAAUAUCUUGAUGUUAAACCAUGAACAGAACCAGCAAGAUCAGCCAGUACCUGAAACCCAAUACAGAGUAGUUCACAGCAAGAAGUACAGAUUGAUCUGGUUCCCAUGCCUGAAACCCUGUCAUCUAGCAGUUCUACCAGUGUUCCUGGGCCAUUUUCUUAGCUUCUUGAGUGAGUUUAGCUCUUUUUGUGUUGACUUUUAGGGCCUCCAGCAGCUCCAUGAUUUUCCAGGACUUUCCAGUCUGGCCCCCACGGAAUUCUCAGGAUGAUUCUCAUCCAGCCCUAAGUCAUGUUUCUAGCCUGGCUCCAGCGGGUAAGCCAGGCCCUGAGAACCAUAUGAAAGGGCUCUCCAGAUAAAAUCAGAGUGCUAAUGCCAGAAUGCUGCAGUAGCCUCCGUUUGUCCACAGGCUCACUGUCUGAGCCCAGGAUAUUUUUAUGAGUGAAACUGUAAGAUCUUUACACUGGACUUCCUAAAGAUAAAACAAUUAUGGAAAUACAGAACUUUACAGAUGAAGCUGUCUAGCCCUAUACAUGUGAAAAUUAAGAUCCAACUACUUCCUGUAAUGGUAGCCUUCCCCUAUGCCUCUAACCCUUUUUUAAAUCCUGAUUUCAAUCACAGGCAUUGUGAUUCUCCAAAGCUCUAACUCUUCCUUAGGUCUGAAAGCCACAUGCUAUCAAUCAUUGAAAUCAAGAGAGAAGGCAUCCGUAGACGGGCGCAGCCCAGUCUUUCCACAUAGCCCAGUUCCUCCCCAGCCACUCCCCAUGGGAAUGACCUCUGCAGCUGACCUAAGCUUAUCCUCUCCUUCUUCCUAAGAGUGCAACUUAGAAGUCAGAGCCAAAUCCUAGAAUGUAUCCCUAAAUGCCAUUUCUAUUUUUUAUAAACAUGAAAAGGUUGUGCUUUGGAAAUUCAGUCUGUUUGAGAACUGGCAGUCUGGCUGGCACUGUUUAAAAAUGUUUAUUUGCCCUGCAUUUAAAAACUGAAGGUUUCCUAUGUAUUAAAAGCCAUAUUUCCACCUUCUUAAGGGAAAAAAAAAUCGGACGUCAUAACACUGGGUGGAUGUUUUUAUGGUAACAGUGGUCUGAGGCCCUUGGCGGAUGCUCACCGAGCCACUGUCACUAUCCUGCCUGCCUUUAUCUGCCUUGCCCUGCGAUUAUUUGGCUUUGUAAGCAUAAGCUACGUAAGACAUACCACACCUAAGAAACUAAACAGCAAUGAAAACCCAUACUUCUGAAAAGGGUGUCUUUUAAAAAUUAAGUUUGAUCUUUUGGGAAAUAAAGCACAUAGUUUUCAAAAUGAUUUACCAAGAUCUAUGCUCUUUCAAAUGGAGACUGGGAUAUUGUUGUUUUGAGACCACUGUUUUCCUGUUUCCUCCCAAAUGUUAGUCACAUAUAUGAUUACCCUUAAGUUGGUCACUAUCUAUCUAUCUGUCAAUAAUUUAGGAUUAAAGUUUGAAGUGUAAUUACAUUUGACUUUUACAGGCAUCUCAGGGUGGACUUCUUAUGAAUACACUGAACCUAUACAAAUGAUCUUAGAAAACGUUUAAUAUCAGAUUUCUUUAUUUUUUCCAACACAACUGAAUCAGUUUUCUUAAAUAAAAGUUUAUUGUCUACUGUUUA